GACUCGAACUCCACCGCGGAAAAGAAAGCCUCAGAACGUUCGUUCGCUGCGUCCCCAGCCGGGGCCGAGCCCUCCGCGACGCCAGCCGGGCCAUGGGGGCCGCACGCAGCCCGCCGUCCGCUGUCCCGGGGCCCCUGCUGGGGCUGCUCCUGCUGCUCCUGGGCGUGCUGGCCCCGGGUGGCGCCUCCCUGCGACUCCUGGACCACCGGGCGCUGGUCUGCUCCCAGCCGGGGCUAAACUGCACGGUCAAGAAUAGUACCUGCCUGGAUGACAGCUGGAUUCACCCUCGAAACCUGACCCCCUCCUCCCCAAAGGACCUGCAGAUCCAGCUGCACUUUGCCCACACCCAACAAGGAGACCUGUUCCCCGUGGCUCACAUCGAAUGGACACUGCAGACAGACGCCAGCAUCCUGUACCUCGAGGGUGCAGAGUUAUCUGUCCUGCAGCUGAACACCAAUGAACGUUUGUGCGUCAGGUUUGAGUUUCUGUCCAAACUGAGGCAUCACCACAGGCGGUGGCGUUUUACCUUCAGCCACUUUGUGGUUGACCCUGACCAGGAAUAUGAGGUGACCGUUCACCACCUGCCCAAGCCCAUCCCUGAUGGGGACCCAAACCACCAGUCCAAGAAUUUCCUUGUGCCUGACUGUGAGCACGCCAGGAUGAAGGUAACCACGCCAUGCAUGAGCUCAGGCAGCCUGUGGGACCCCAACAUCACCGUGGAGACCCUGGAGGCCCACCAGCUGCGUGUGAGCUUCACCCUGUGGAACGAAUCUACCCAUUACCAGAUCCUGCUGACCAGUUUUCCGCACAUGGAGAACCACAGUUGCUUUGAGCACAUGCACCACAUACCUGCGCCCAGACCAGAAGAGUUCCACCAGCGAUCCAACGUCACACUCACUCUACGCAACCUUAAAGGGUGCUGUCGCCACCAAGUGCAGAUCCAGCCCUUCUUCAGCAGCUGCCUCAAUGACUGCCUCAGACACUCCGCGACUGUUUCCUGCCCAGAAAUGCCAGACACUCCAGAACCAAUUCCGGACUACAUGCCCCUGUGGGUGUACUGGUUCAUCACGGGCAUCUCCAUCCUGCUGGUGGGCUCCGUCAUCCUGCUCAUCGUCUGCAUGACCUGGAGGCUAGCUGGGCCUGGAAGUGAAAAAUACAGUGAUGACACCAAAUACACCGAUGGCCUGCCUGCGGCUGACCUGAUCCCCCCACCGCUGAAGCCCAGGAAGGUCUGGAUCAUCUACUCAGCCGACCACCCCCUCUACGUGGACGUGGUCCUGAAAUUCGCCCAGUUCCUGCUCACCGCCUGCGGCACGGAAGUGGCCCUGGACCUGCUGGAAGAGCAGGCCAUCUCGGAGGCAGGAGUCAUGACCUGGGUGGGCCGUCAGAAGCAGGAGAUGGUGGAGAGCAACUCUAAGAUCAUCGUCCUGUGCUCCCGCGGCACGCGCGCCAAGUGGCAGGCGCUCCUGGGCCGGGGGGCGCCUGUGCGGCUGCGCUGCGACCACGGAAAGCCCGUGGGGGACCUGUUCACUGCAGCCAUGAACAUGAUCCUCCCGGACUUCAAGAGGCCAGCCUGCUUCGGCACCUACGUAGUCUGCUACUUCAGCGAGGUCAGCUGUGACGGCGACGUCCCCGACCUGUUCGGCGCGGCGCCGCGGUACCCGCUCAUGGACAGGUUCGAGGAGGUGUACUUCCGCAUCCAGGACCUGGAGAUGUUCCAGCCGGGCCGCAUGCACCGCGUAGGGGAGCUGUCGGGGGACAACUACCUGCGGAGCCCGGGCGGCAGGCAGCUCCGCGCCGCCCUGGACAGGUUCCGGGACUGGCAGGUCCGCUGUCCCGACUGGUUCGAAUGUGAGAACCUCUACUCAGCAGAUGACCAGGAUGCCCCGUCCCUGGACGAAGAGGUGUUUGAGGAGCCACUGCUGCCUCCGGGAACCGGCAUCGUGAAGCGGGCGCCCCUGGUGCGCGAGCCUGGCUCCCAGGCCUGCCUGGCCAUAGACCCGCUGGUCGGGGAGGAAGGAGGAGCAGCAGUGGCAAAGCUGGAACCUCACCUGCAGCCCCGGGGUCAGCCAGCGCCGCAGCCCCUCCACACCCUGGUGCUCGCCGCAGAGGAGGGGGCCCUGGUGGCCGCGGUGGAGCCUGGGCCCCUGGCUGACGGUGCCGCAGUCCGGCUGGCACUGGCGGGGGAGGGCGAGGCCUGCCCGCUGCUGGGCAGCCCGGGCGCUGGGCGAAAUAGCGUCCUCUUCCUCCCCGUGGACCCCGAGGACUCGCCCCUUGGCAGCAGCACCCCCAUGGCGUCUCCUGACCUCCUUCCAGAGGACGUGAGGGAGCACCUCGAAGGCUUGAUGCUCUCGCUCUUCGAGCAGAGUCUGAGCUGCCAGGCCCAGGGGGGCUGCAGUAGACCCGCCAUGGUCCUCACAGACCCACACACGCCCUACGAGGAGGAGCAGCGGCAGUCAGUGCAGUCUGACCAGGGCUACAUCUCCAGGAGCUCCCCGCAGCCCCCCGAGGGACUCACGGAAAUGGAGGAAGAGGAGGAAGAGGAGCAGGACCCAGGGAAGCCGGCCCUGCCACUCUCUCCCGAGGACCUGGAGAGCCUGAGGAGCCUCCAGCGGCAGCUGCUUUUCCGCCAGCUGCAGAAGAACUCGGGCUGGGACACGAUGGGGUCAGAGUCAGAGGGGCCCAGUGCAUGAGGGCGGCUCCCCAGGGACCGCCCAGAUCCCAGCUUUGAGAGAGGAGUGUGUGUGCACGUAUUCAUCUGUGUGUACAUGUCUGCAUGUGUAUAUGUUCGUGUGUGAAAUGUAGGCUUUAAAAUGUAAAUGUCUGGAUUUUAAUCCCAGGCAUCCCUCCUAACUUUUCUUUGUGCAGCGGUCUGGUUAUCGUCUAUCCCCAGGGGAAUCCACACAGCCCGCUCCCAGGAGCUAAUGGUAGAGCGUCCUUGAGGCUCCAUUAUUCGUUCAUUCAGCAUUUAUUGUGCACCUACUAUGUGGCGGGCAUUUGGGAUACCAAGAUAAAUUGCAUGCGGCAUGGCCCCAGCCAUGAAGGAACUUAACCGCUAGUGCCGAGGACACGUUAAACGAACAGGAUGGGCCGGGCACGGUGGCUCACGCCUGUAAUCCCAGCACACUGGGAGGCCGAGGCAGGUGGAUCACUCUGAGGUCAGGAGUUUGAGCCAGCCUGGCCAACAUGGUGAAACCCCAUCUCCACUAAAAAUAGAAAAAUUAGCCGGGCAUGGUGACACAUGCCUGUAGUCCUAGCUACUUGGGAGGCUGAGGCAGGAGAAUUGCUUGAAUCUGGGAGGCAGAGGUUGCAGUGAGCCGAGAUUGUGCCAUUGCACUGCAGCCUGGAUGACAGAGCGAGACUCUAUCUCAAAAAAAAAAAAAAAAAAAGAUGGUCACGCGGGAUGUAAACGCUGAAUGGGCCAGGUGCAGUGGCUCAUGCUUGUAAUCCCAGCACUUUGGGAAGGCGAGGCAGGUGGAUUGCUUGAGCUCAGGAGUUCAAGACCAGCCUGGGCGACAUAGUGAGACCUCAUCUCUACCUAAAUUUUUUUUUAGUCAGUCAUGGUGGCACAUGCCUGUAGUCCCAGCUACUCGGGAGGCUGAUGCCAGAUGAUCACUUGAGCCCAGGAGGUAGAGGCUGCAGUGAGCUAUAAUGGUACCAUUGCAAUCCAGCCUGGGCAGCAGAGUGAGACCCUGUCUCAAAAAAAAUAAAAAAGUAGAAAGAUGGAGUGGAAGCCUGCCCAGGGUUGUGAGCAUGCACGGGAAAGGCACCCAGGUCAGGGGGGAUCCCCGAGGAGAUGCCUGAGCUGAAGGAUUGUGGUUGGGGAAAGCGUAGUCCCAGCAAGGAAGCAGUUUGUGGGUAAGUGCUGGGAGGUGAGUGGAGUGAGCUUGUCAGGGAGCUGCUGGUGGAGCCUGGAGGGGAAGGAGGGAGGCAGUGAGAGAGAUCGGGGUGGGGGGUGGGGGGAUGUCGCCAGAGCUCAGGGGUGGGGACAGCCUUGUGCGCAUCAGUCCUGAGGCCUGGGGCACCUUUCGUCUGAUGAGCCUCUGCAUGGAGAGAGGCUGAGGGCUAAACACAGCUGGAUGUCACCUGAGUUCAUUUAUAGGAAGAGAGAAAUGUCGAGGUGAAACGUAAAAGCAUCUGGCAGGAAGGUGAGUCUGAAGCCCUGCACCCGCGUUCCGACUAUCAGUGGGGAGCUGUUAGCACGUAGGAUUCUUCAGAGCAGCUGGGCUGGAGCUCCCCUGAGCUCAGGAAGCCCCAGGGUGCAAGGGCAAGGAAAUGAGGGGUGGUGGGUCAGUGAAGAUCUGGGCAGACCUUGUGUGGGGAAGGGGUGCUGCUGUGACUUCAGGGUCUGAGGUCCAAAGACAGCAUUUGAAAAGAGGCUCUGAAGCCAGUGUUUGAAGAAUUUGUUCCUGAAGUACCUCCUGGGGGUAGGCUAGAGGCUUCUGGCUUCAGGGUCCUGAAGAACACAUUGAGGUGCCGUCUGACACUGGAAUAGGGUGCCCUUCAUUCCUAUGCCUGAGUCCUUAACUAUAUUUCCAACCUCCAGUGAGGAGGAGAAGAUUCGGAAAUGUGACAGGAGAGCAAACAGGACAGUUUGCAUGUGUGUGUGCGCACACAUACAUGUGCGUGAAAGAUUAUCAAUAAAAGUGCAUAAAUUUGUUGAUCUGGUAAGAGUUUCUAGCAGGAAGGUCGAGCCACUUACUGUAGGUCAAGAAGUUGCUAGUUGCGGAGUUUUUUCUUGCAGUUAGACUUUACCUAGUGGUAGCAGGGCCACCAAAGCUCUGUGUCCCAGAUGGUGUAUGGCCCAUAAUCCACCCAACAGCAGCAAAGGACCAGGCAAAGGAGAACAGGAGCAGAAGCCUCCCAGCCACUAGCCUUUUGGGCUCAGUCUCUCCAAUAAUCCUGGAGAGGGGCUUCGUUGGGUCUGGACACCUACCAUGCAUUCUGUGACCUUUCCCUAGCUUCCAAUAAAUAACUGUUUGACGCCCAGAGUACAGGAUACCACAAUGCACUCUUCCUGCGUAGAGCACAUGUUCCCAUCUGCUCCCAUUCCUCAGGAACCUUGAAUUCUAGCUCUGCUGGCCUUUGAGCCCAUGCCAGUAAAUGUCCUGAUGGGCAUUGCCUACUAUCUCCAGGGCAGCUGCCUUUGUCCUCCUAACAGCUUUAUUGGAGUACAGUUCACUUACCAUACAAUCCACAAUUGACCCUGCACAAUUUGAUGCCGGUUUAGUAUAGUCACAGUUCAGCAGCCAUCAGCACAGUCAGUCUUAGAGUUUACUACCCCCAAAAGAAAUCCAGCCCCCCUUAGUCACCACCCCAACCUCCCCAUCCCUAGGCACCCCUAGGCUACUUUGAUCUCUGUAGACUUGCCUCUUCUGGACAUGACAUAGAGAAAGGAGUCAUAAAUUCUCCAAGGUGUCUGUUUCUUCUUUAAUGUCAUUCCCUGUUUCUCCUCACAUUCCCUCCCCAUUUCCUGGGCCCAGUCUCACACUGGUCCUUGCUUACCCUAAAUGCUAUUAAUUCCAUCACUCUGAGUAUGGUGUUUGCUGUCCGCUGAAUGCCAAGAGCUUCAAGAGUGUGUGUAAAUAAAGCCACACCUUUAUUUUUGUAUUAUUCUGAACCAUGGCUAAUAAAUUGUUUCACCAAGAAAUGUCUCUCUAAGAACAGGUGCCCUCCACGCUGUGCCCCUCCCACCUCUUCAGCUCGUCUCCUGAGUGUGCAGAGGUGGUUCCGGUUGGGAAAGAAGCAGCGGAGCAUCUAACCAUGCCUGUGUCCAGGCCGAUUAUGCACGCAGCCACCAACAAGCUCCCAACUCCCGCGUAGAGUUUCAUGACUUUUUCCUGCCUACUAUCUUGAUCCUAGUUUUUUUUUUGUUUUUUUUUUUUUUAAGGAAUAAUUACUUUGAUUCAAAACCAGUUUCUCUUUUCUGCAUAGGAAGGUCCUUGAAGGUGUUUAGGGUCUAAAAAGGGUGGUGUUCGGUCUCUGAAACAUCCAUUCAGCAGUUUGAGCUGGGAUCUCUGAAUGCAAGGGUAUGAUGGAUAUACUUCUUUCUUGCUUUUGUUGUGUUUUGGUUUUUUGUUUGUUUUUAAGUCAGGGUCUCUCUGUCACCAGGCUGUAUUACAGUGGUGCAAUCAUGGCUCACUGCAGCCUCGACCUCCCAGGCUCAAGCCAUCUUUCCACCUCAGCCUGCCAGUGGCUAGAACUACAGGCGUGCACCACUGUGCCCGGCUAAUUUGUGUGUAUAUAUUUUGUAGAAAUGGGGUUUCACCAUGUUGUCCAGGCUGGUCACGAACUCCUGGGCUCAAGCCAUCUGCCCGCCUCAUCCUCCCAAAGUGCUGGGAUUAUAGGCCUGAGCCCACCGUGCCUGGCCUUUCCUGUUUAUCUUUGAAAAUUAAAUAGGGCAUAAGAGAGAAGAAGAUGUACUUACAAUGCAGUGGGUGGUUUUAACUCUAUAGCCUUUGGGCUCUGUGGUUGGUGCUCCCCUUCCUAAAUAAAUGAGGUGUAUGCAGGGCCCUCUUCUGCCUUAGCGCCCUGCCAGCUGGGACUCCAGCAAGGCCCGGGGCACCUGAGGACAGAGUGAGAUGGAGGGCCGCUGCUCCAGCAGCCGGGCCUGCAUCCCACAAGUCAACUGUGUCGGACAGAGGAUCCUUACAAAGAAGAGGCAGCAGGGUUGGGGGCUGGCCAGCUGCUCGUCCGCCCUAGGUAGCUUGCUCAUCUGUAAAGUGGGUGGGGCAGGAGUUCCCACCUCAUGGGGUCCUGGCAAGCCUGCAGUAUCCCCGAGUGGCACCAGCCUGCUUCUGGGGCAGAGCAGUUUGUGCCCCCUGAGGUACCACUGAUCCUCUUUCCCUGCUAUUAGGUAUUGCUCUCUUCCUCCGGUGUUUGCCUUUUCAGAUUAUAGAAGUAAUAUGUGUUCCCAUAUUUGGCGUCUCUCAGGAGCUCAGGAAGUACUUGGCUGAGUGAACAUGUCCAUUGUGGAAAAAUGGCAACAAUAUGGAUUCCAUGGGUAUAUUUUAUAGAAGAAUAUGAAGAAAAGCAGCUACCCCUAAACCCAUUGCACAAGCUGUUCAUGUUAAUUCUGUACCCGACGCUUUCCCCACGGGGCCUCCCCUCACUCUGAAAUGGCAUCCAGGUCCAUCUUGCCCUCCACCUCUGCAUGGCUCUCCAUGCCCCAUCGCCUCUCCCAGAUCCUAGCACUGGGUCCACACUCUCGCCCUGUCCAUUUAGGUUGAUGAAAGCAGGCAGUCACCCGGGUGGGCCAGUCUUGCCUGUGGGAGGAACAUGCAGUCUCCUGUCUCAUGGUUUGAAGUGUGCCAGGAAGCCUGGCCCAGCCCACCUCCCCCUGGAGUCCUUCCCAGGAGGAAUAACCCCUUAGGUCAUUGACUAUAAGAUGAGUUCGCUCACUGGAUCCUUCCUCUCUGAUGAGACAGGAAGAAGGUACACAGUGACCAGGUAGGAGGAGGAGAGGGAGUAGAAAGGAGGGAUGCGGGUGGCUGGUCCCUGCAUUUGCCUGCUUCCCUGCACGGGUGUCCCACUGGCCGCCUCUGCUCACCAGUGUCAUGGGAUUCUCUCAGAAGAUGAAAACAGCCCCUGCUUUUUUGCUAGAAUGGCUGAGCUUUCAUGGAAAGGAAGCUGGACCCAAGCAACAGCCGACUACCGAAGGUUGCCUGGAGCAGUGCAGAUGUGGGAGGAAGAAGGGCCUUGGUGCACACUGGCUUUUCUUCCUGACUGCAAUGUGGCAUUGUGCCAGCUACCUCCUCUUUCUCGGCCUCAGGAAAAUGGAGAGAAAGCAGCCCUGAAGGUGGCUGUGACGAGGGAAGGGGCAGAGGGCCUGACAGUCAACCACGCGCUAUAUUUUCCUGUUCUUCCUUAGGGCAAGAACUGCAUGGCCAGACUCAGGCAAGGCCUAGGUGUGGGCUGGGCAUUGCCUACACGUGAAGAGAUCACUCCGCGUCCCUACUGCACCUGUCACAAAGUGCCUUCUGAUAUGCCUGGCAAACCAAAAUCGGUGAGCGCCAGCUUGCUUCCCUAGAAGACAUUUCUAAAUAUUCAUAACAUGCUUGCUCAAAUCAAUCACCUUAUUUUACAUCCGCUCCAGGGAGAAAUGAAGACAUGGUCCUACGUUGUUCUGUAAUUAUUUUCUAUGUAAAUUUUGUUCCUUGUUACAAUUAUAUAUGUCUUAGGGGAAAGGACCAUUUCACAUGUGUCACCUCAUGUGAUUCUCACCACAGCCCUGUGAUUGCUCCUGUUUUAUAAAUAAUGACAUAGUUCCAGUUGAUGGCCAAAGCCACAGCUAACGAGAGGCAGAGAGAGCUCAGGCUCCCAGGAGCUUCCACUCUCAGACCUUGCCUCCCGGGCUGCCCUGAGUGAAACGCCUGCUUAGCAUUUGGCACAGCCAGAAGCAGCAAGCUAGGGUCACAACACAGAGAGGGGCUGUGUAAUACUGGCUGCCUCUGUGCUAAGAAAAAAAAAAAAUCACUGUGUGUUUGUUUAUUUUGGUGCAGGCCCAGUGUUCUUGCUUAGACUUAAUACUACCCUUCAUGUUAAAAUAAAACCAAACAAAAACCCA